AUUUCCGGGGUAAGAUGGCUGCAGUCCGUAUGCUGAGAACCUGGAGCAGGAAUGCGGGGAAGCUGAUGCUCCUGCCUUGGUGACCCCGAUCUUACAAAAACUUUCAAGAGCCUGCUAUGUACCAGUGCUGUGUUAGGCACUGGAGAUACAAAUAUGAAAUAGACAUCAUAUCUUCCUUCUCAAGAGAUUACAACCUUGUGGUGGAGGACAAAGGAGAGGGAGACAGAUAGAAAUUACAACCCAGCAUGAGAGGCACCCACCGGGGGAUCUUGAACGUGUCCACUGCACAUAAGGAGAUAAGAGAGGAAUACGAUUUGUGUUCGCUAUUUUCAAACAUGUGGUAAUGUUCAUGUUUUGAAGCCAAAUUAUGUGUGUUUCUUUGGUUAUCCUUCAUUCAAGUAUAGUCAUCCACAUCACUUCCUGAAAACAACUGCUGCUCUCCGUGGACAGGUUGUUCAGUUCAAGCUCUCAGACAUUGGAGAAGGGAUUAGAGAAGUAACUGUUAAAGAAUGGUAUGUAAAAGAAGGAGAUACAGUGUCUCAGUUUGAUAGCAUCUGUGAAGUUCAAAGUGAUAAAGCUUCUGUUACCAUCACUAGUCGUUAUGAUGGAGUCAUUAAAAAACUCUAUUAUAAUCUAGACGAUAUUGCCUAUGUGGGGAAGCCAUUAGUAGACAUAGAAACGGAAGCUUUAAAAGAUUCAGAAGAAGAUGUUGUUGAAACUCCUGCAGUGUCUCAUGAUGAACAUACACACCAAGAGAUAAAGGGCCGAAAAACACUGGCAACUCCUGCAGUUCGCCGUCUGGCAAUGGAAAACAAUAUUAAGCUGAGUGAAGUUGUUGGCUCAGGAAAAGAUGGCAGAAUACUUAAAGAAGAUAUCCUCAACUAUUUGGAAAAGCAGACAGGAGCUAUAUUGCCUCCUUCACCCAAAGUUGAAAUUAUGCCACCUCCACCAAAGCCAAAAGACAUGACUGUUCCUAUACUAGUAUCAAAACCUCCGGUAUUCACAGGCAAAGACAAAACAGAACCCAUAAAAGGCUUUCAAAAAGCAAUGGUCAAGACUAUGUCUGCAGCCCUGAAGAUACCUCAUUUUGGUUAUUGUGAUGAGAUUGACCUUACUGAACUGGUUAAGCUCCGAGAAGAAUUAAAACCCAUUGCAUUUGCUCGUGGAAUUAAACUCUCCUUUAUGCCUUUCUUCUUAAAGGCUGCUUCCUUGGGAUUACUACAGUUUCCUAUCCUUAACGCUUCUGUGGAUGAAAACUGCCAGAAUAUAACAUAUAAGGCUUCUCAUAACAUUGGGAUAGCAAUGGAUACUGAGCAGGGUUUGAUUGUCCCUAAUGUGAAAAAUGUUCAGAUCUGCUCUAUAUUUGACAUCGCCACUGAACUGAACCGCCUCCAGAAAUUGGGCUCUGUGAGUCAGCUCAGCACCACUGAUCUUACAGGAGGAACAUUUACUCUUUCCAACAUUGGAUCAAUUGGUGGUACCUUUGCCAAACCAGUGAUAAUGCCACCUGAAGUAGCCAUUGGGGCCCUUGGAUCAAUUAAGGCCAUUCCCCGAUUUAACCAGAAAGGAGAAGUAUAUAAGGCACAGAUAAUGAAUGUGAGCUGGUCAGCUGAUCACAGAGUUAUUGAUGGUGCUACAAUGUCACGCUUCUCCAAUUUGUGGAAAUCCUAUUUAGAAAACCCAGCUUUUAUGCUACUAGAUCUGAAAUGAAGACUGAUAAGACAUUCUUGAACUUUUUGAGCUUCCAAAGAGUAUGUAAACCCUAGCUGUGCCAGCACAUGUUCAUCUUUACAAUUUAUAUUGUAAAUGAUUUGUAUCGUAUGAUUAAGGAUCUAAGGCACAAUAUUUGUCACUGUUCUAUUAGACUUUUUACUGAAAAUGAAUAAUGGUGUAAUGGUUCUCCUGGGGCUGUCACAUUUUAUAGGUCAGAGUGUGACUUCUUAAUAUGGUGCUGAUGUUUUUGUGUCAAUGGCUUGAAACUGGCAAGAUUAACAAAAUUAGGCCGGGCAUGGUGGCUCACGCCUGUAAUCCCAGCACUUUGGGAGGCCCAGGUGGGCGGAUCACCUGAGGUUAGAAGUUUGAGACCAGCCUGGCCAACAUGGUGAAACCUGGCCUCUACUAAAAAUACAAAAAUUAGCCGGGUGUGGUGGUGGGUACCUAUAAUCCCAGCUACUUGGGAGGCUGAGGCAGGAGAAUCGCUUGAACCUGGGAGGUGGAGGUUGCAGUGAGCUGAGAUCGUGCUAUUGCACUCCAGCCUGGGCGACAGAGCAAGACGCCAUCUCAAAAACAAAAAAACAAAAUUCAUGUUACUAAAAGACAGGUAGCCAUAUACAGACAGUAUAUGCCCUAUUUUUUUUAACUGACUCUUAAUGAAACUUUAAUUUUACUUAAUUAAGAAAUGGAAUUUAUAUACAAAAAUAUUUUCCAUUUCCGUUAUUAUGCUAAUUGUUGUAUGAAAUAAGUGCAAUUAUACUUCUCUUUUGAGAUAUCCAAGAGUAUAUUCUUGCUCUGUAUAGAGAAUAUCAUCUGAUAGUGUCUUAUUUAUAUUAAUUAAUGUCUUUGAAAAGGGAAAAGUAUAAACUGGCCUUAAAAUUGUCCAAUUAUAGUUUUAUAACCAGUCUAUUAAAGGUGUUUGUUUAAAAUGGAUAUAGUUUUAGAUUUGUGGUAAUGCUUUGGUAUUUUCUUGGGGAAGACCUUCACCUUUGCAAACUUCCCUCAUGUAAGGAAGGUACUUUAAAUGUAGCAGCCACUGACAUUUCUUUUUUUAAAAAAAAUUUGAGAAGUCUACUUCCUUUUAACUUUUUUGGUCUUCAGCUAAAAAAUAGGAUAAGAAAUUAAGGUCUAUUCCAUUCUCCAUAUCCUGGGUAAGAAUGUAAAUAAGAGGAGAAGGAAGAGUCUAAUAGUAAUUAUGGAUAUAAAAAAUAAGAAAUUUUGUAUAGAAAUGAAGGUUUCAUAAUGAUCAUUUUGUUAAAGGUCUACUUUAAUCAGAAAUAGCAACGAGAUGAAUGUAUCCAACAUUUCAAUUUGCAUUCGGAAAUCCAUGUUGUUUCUAAUAUUGUCCAGUUGAAAACUGUAUGCCAAAAUUAGUUGUUUAAGUGAAGUUUUGUGACAGAAAAAAGGUUGUUUUAAUAUCUACUUGGUUUUUCUCAAAAUGGAAAUAAUUUUAAAAUCAGGAAAGAAUAAAUCAGCCAGGUGUGAUGACUUGUAACUGUAAUCCCAGUUAUAGGGGAGGCUGAAGCAGGAGGAUCACUUGAGGCCAGGAGUUUGAGACCAGCCUGGGCAACAUAGUGAGAUCCCAUCUCAAAAAACAUUAUUUUUAAAAUUAGCCUGGUGGCUCACGCCUGUAAUCCCAGCACUUUGGGAGGCCGAGGUGGCCAGAUCACCUGAGGUCAGGAGUUCGAGACCACCCUGGCCAACAUGGUGAAACCCCAUCUCUACAGUUUUGUAAAAAUACAAAAAAUUACCUGGGCCUGGUGGCACACGCCUGUAGUCCCAGCUACUUGGGAGGCUGAGGCAGGAGAAUUGCUUGAGCCCAAGAGGUGGAGGUUACAGUGAGCAGAGAUCACACCACUGCACUCCAGCCUGGGUGGCAGAGCAACACUUUGUCUCAGAAAAAAAAAAAAAAACCAAAAAGCCAAGUGUGGUGGUGUGCACCUAUAGUCCCAGCUACUCAGGAAGCUGAGACAAGAGGAUCAAUUGAGCCCAGGAGUUCAAAGCUGUAGUGAGCUGUCAUUGUGCCACUAUCCUCCAGUAUGGGUGACAGAGUGAGACCUGGUCUCUAAAAAAUAAAAUAAAAUAAAAAAAACAGGUCAAAUAAAUGCUGUUGUUGUAAAAUUUCAGAUAAUACAAAGAGUUAACCAAUAAAAGAAAAAGUCAUUCAUAAUCUUACCACUAUUAACAUUUUGAUGUAUCUAUCUGUAUGUAUGGCUAUUCUUUUUUGUUAAAACAUGAUCAUAGCAUAUCUACUAUUUUAUUAUUUGAUUUUUAAAAUUUAACAUUAUAUUAUGGGUAACCUUACAUGUCAAUAAACAAUUCCACAUUGUCAUGCUUUAAAUGGCUGCAUAGGCUGGGUGUGGUGGCUCACGCCUGUAAUCCUACCACUUUGGGAGGCCAAGGCAGGUAGAUCACAAGGUCAGGAGUUCGAGACCAGCCUGGCCAAUAUGGUGAAACCUCAUCUCUAUUGAAAAUACAAAAAUCAGCCAGGCACGGUGGCAGGCGCCUGUAGUCCACCUACUCGGGAGGCUGAGGCAGGAGAACUGCUUGAACCCAGCGGCAGAGGUUGCAGUGAGCCAAGAUUGAGCCACUGCACUCCAGCCUGGUGAUAGAGCGAGACUCUGUCUCUAAAUAAAUAAAUAAAUAAAUAAAUGUCUGCAUAGUAUUCCAUUGUAUGCAUUUAUUAUACAUUCAAACAUUAAACAUCUACCAUACCAAUCAUGGUUCUAAGCAUACAGUAGCCACCUUCAUGCUUCCUUGAUUGGGCUUACAGUCUAGUAAGGAGACAGAUAUUAAAUAACUGCAUAAAACACUGUUCUUGGUAGGUAAUAACCCAGAUGCUAUGAGCCAUCCAGUAAAGGUUACCGAUCUUAUCUGGAAGGAUCAGAAGAUGGAUGUCCCAUAAUUUAACCAAUUAUCUAUUGAUAGGCAUUUAUUGAGUUUUAAAUGAAUAAUGACAUGAUCAAUAAAAAUGUCCUCCUCACUUAAAGAAUAGAAAAACCAGGAGAAGGGAGUUCUGAAAUAAGUAAGUAUGUAGGUCCAGCAUCAAUGGCUCAAGAUACUCUAUUCCCAAAUAACCCUUAAGUUAUCUGGUUCUAUUCCAACCCUUGGGUAUUACUAUCUUCUCUUUGGUCUCAUGCAUUGAGAAUUCAGCAAAGGAUUUGUUCCCUACAGUGUGCACGGCCCUUAGGAUAGCAGGAUUCCCUGAAGAGGGCCAAAGGGGCAGGAGCGCAGCCUUAGUGGCAGUGCUGGUCCAUGAGGCUCUACAAAGCAAGGGAUGGGUGUUUGGGAGGAGGAAAAGGCUCUUGCUGUACUCCUAGAGGUUGGAAUUAAAGUGGAAAAGCCAGAAAAUUCAAGUCCUUUACUAACAUGUCUGGAGAUUAGAAGGUAUAUGUACAUGGGGGAGAAGCCAAAAUUAUUGCUGCGAGUGGUCAGCAAGAAAAUCAAGGCUCUUUUCAUUAUUUUGAGCAUUCCUCUGAUAUUUGAAAAGGAAGUACAACAGGAAAGGAAGUCUGAGGAUGGAAGCUAAAAUUGGUAUGAAUUUAUAUUUUAGAGAUCAAAAUGUACCUUAUGUUGAAACCUAUGUAAGAAGUGAUUAUGUAGAAAGAGUGAAAGUGAUAGCUCUUAGUCUGGAAAGCCCACUGGCUUGUUUGGGCAUUUCUCAUGGCUUCCCACUCAAAGUGGAUCCCCAAAAUCACUUGAUGGAUUUCCUUGCUGAUUUCUAAGUAAACUAUGGUUUAAGAAAGAAAUGACAGGGCUCAGCACUGCCCUACAGUACCAAGAAUACAAAUGUUUCCAUGAAGUCUUCAAAGGCAUUUGUAAAAUUCAGGCUGUAAGUGAUUAGUUAGUUCAUUCUGCACUUAUUUAUUAACUGUAUAUUCAGUUCCAGGCUCUAGGGUAGAGAUUAUGGAUAAAGGUGAAUUAGAUAGAUGAAGUUUUUGCCCUCACAGCAAAAGCUUUAGCCAAUAAUUAAAGCUAUCACUGGAAGUGGGUCUGUGCCAAUAACCUAGAGAAGAGCAGUGCUUUUAGAGUUGAGCUAUAUUCCCAAUCAGUUCUUAAUGGUGGUUUUACCCCCUUCCCUCUACACUGUCUUUUCUUGAGAUUGGAUCAUGUGUGUGAACCCACAUCAUUUCCAGUCAAAAUCACCAAGAGAGGCCGGACACAGUGGCUCAUGCCUAUAAUCCCAGCACUUUGGGAGGCCUAAAUGGGUGGGCCUCUUGAGUCCAGAGUUUGAGACCAGCCUGGGCGACCCCAGCUCUACCAAAAAAACCAAAAAACAAAAAAUACCAAAAAAAAAAAAAAUUAGGCCGAUGAAGUGACAUGCACCUGUGUGCCACCUACUCAGGAGGCUGAGGUGGCAGGAUCACUUGCAUCUGGGGGCAAAGGCUGCCGUGAGCUGAGAUUGUGCCAUUGCGCUCCAGCCUGGGCGACAGAGCAAGACUCUGUGUGUGUGUGUGUGUGUGUGUGUGUGUGUGUGUGUGUGUGUGUGUGUGUGUGUGUGUAUACACACACACAUAUAUAUACACACACCCCCAGGAGACCUUUUGUCUUUCUUGGUUCAUGUGCCCAUCAGUGUGGGCAGGAGAAUAGAAUACUCUGUCCACACUUGAGUCUUAGUCACCUUUGGAGCCUAGGAGUCAGCCAUCCUCAUUCAACUACAUGGAUCGAGAAUGGGAAUCUGGGAGAAUUUUUUUAUGGGCAGAUUAAAAAGGAAGUUAACUAUGUAAAGUAAGGCAUUGCCUUCCCACCCCAUCCCACCUCAGUUCGUGUUAAAUUAUGAAUUUUUCUAAGAGAGUUCUUUAAUGACAUGGAUAGAGAGGAAGCUGAGGUGGCAGUAGAGUAGGGAGUGGAAGGCAAAUACAUAAGAUACUAUUAAACUGUGAAGCUGUUUGUUACAAUUCCAAGAUUUUAUAAUUUCUCCAACAAAAAACAUUUGUAUUUUCUUCCCAGUUUAAGUUCAAUGUUAAUUUGAGAAAUAAUUCUACUCUCAAACUUCAUGUUAUGCUGACAGUUCAACUGAUGCUGUCAAAAUGUGAAUUACUAACUUCAGUAUUCUCUAUUCAUCUGAUUUUUCUUAAAAUGUUUGCGUGUUAAUAUACUCACUAGCUUUAAUGCUCUACUCUUAUACUGGCACCUUAAUUAUGGUAAAAGGUAAAAGGUUAAGUUAAAAUUCCCAAUCCUAGUUAUUUGGUCAAACAGAAGAUUAACAGAACUCCAUGGCUUACCACAGGAAUAUUUAUCAAGAGAAAAAGAAGAUACCUAUUUGAAUUUACAUGACACUUUCUGUGAAAUAUCUGGAUUACCAGAUUAGUCUGAAACAAAUGCCUUCCAAAUUCUACAGCGCAUGCCCAAGGCACUCUUUACAGUACCUGUUCGGGUCUUUUCUUCUAAUUUUAAGCACCUACCCAAACGUCUUCCCAGGCUUGUCAUAAUAAGCAAAUAACCUCAGAGCAGACAAAGUGAUUCAAUCUAAGAACCUUGAAUUUCUCUCCUUUUCACCUCAAAAUUUCUAUUCUCACACUUUCUUUUUGUUUCUCUUUCCGAGAAGUGGUUCUCCAUCAGCAAAUACCAACUGUUUUCUGUCCUCUAUUAUUUAUUCCAUCUCUUCCUCCUGAUCCCUGCCCCAUGUUGAACCCCCAUUGCCCCACUUUGAUCCUUCAGUCUCUUCCUCACAUCCAGAACUGUACCAGAUUUACUCCCUUAGCACACUGAUUAAAAUUUAUUUCCAUUUCCUUAUGGAGGAGGUAUUAGAGACUGAUCCCAGACCUCUACAAAUUUCAUUGUGGCAGGGUAAUGUUAUGUGUCCAUAAACCUUGUUCCUUUUCUUUCAGCCUGCAGUUAGGUAGAGCCAUGUCAUUUAUUUGUAACUAUUAGAAUAUGGGUAUAUGGGUUGAAGUAAUGUAGGCCAUUUCCAGACAUGGCCCAUAACACUUCUCAAGAGAUUCUUCAUAUUCUAUCUCUUCCCCUCCAACAUGCACCCUUCAAGGUUGAAGAUGGCACCACACAAGAUAGAAGGAGCCAGUGUUCCAAAUGACUAGGCAGAGCAGAAUGCUCCCCUCCCUACACCCUAGCACCAAUUGGUUUGGAUGUGAUAGUUGAAUAAUACACUUUUAUUGUUUUAAGACAUUAAUAUUUUGAGAUUAAUCUGCAAGUCUAGUUAGUAAAACUCGAACUCUGAGCUGUCUAAUGCAGUAGCCUCUAGCCACAUGUAGCUAUUUAAAUUUAAAUUUUAAUUUUAAUUAAUCAAAAUUCAACUCAGAUAUACUAGCCACAUUUCAAUUGCUCAGUAGCCACACUAAUUAAAUUUAAAUUUAAAUAGCUACAUGUGGCUUAUAGCACCAUACCAGAUAGCACAGAUGUAGACUGUUUCCAUCAUCACAGAAAAUUCUAUUGGAUAGUGCUGCCUUAACUAAUAAGACACAAAUGUUCUUAUUUUUUAAAUAGUCCCUAAAACAAACGAAAAACAAAGAACUCCCUUCUCUAAUGGCAAAUUUCAGUUUGCCUAAAAGAAGACUCAGAAUGCUUUUCUUAUAUUGUUACCUCUGACUGCCACUAAAUGAAUAAAUUUCCUGUCUUGCUCCUUCUGCCAAACUUCUUGAAUGGGUGAUCUUUAACUCCUUGCAAUCCUGGCUUUUUUCCCCAGUGCUCACCUGUAAUCAGUGUUGGCCACAACUCCCACCCAGAUGUCUCCUAAAUAGUUCUCUGAACCCACCUCUGUCCUGAUCUACAGACAUUCAUUCCAAUGCUUUAGCAUUUCAAGGUCAUCAAAUGACUCAGUGACAUCUCAGACAGUCAGACAGACCAGGUCAACUAUGAACUAUUUAUGCCAAACCUUACAUGGUUCAUGUUAUCCUUGCUAUCCCAUCAAAAUAACCACAGGCUUUUUUUUUUUUUUUUUUUAAUUUUUGAGAUGGAGUCUCACUCUGUCACCCCGACUAGAGUGCAGUGGUGCGAUCUCGGCUCUGCUCACUGCAACCUCCGUCUCCUGGGUUCAAACAGUGCUCAUUCCUCAACUCCCAAGUAGCUGAGAUUACAGGCAUGCACCAUCACGCCUGGCUAAUUUUUCUAUUUUUAGCAGAGAUGGGGUUUCGCCAUGUUGGCCAGGCUGGUCUCGAACUCCUGACCUCAAGUGAUCUGCCCGCCUCCACCUCACAAAGCUUUGGGAUUACAGGCAUGAGCCACGGUGCCUGGCCUGCAGCCUCCUUUAUUUUACAAAAGGCAUUACCACUUAAACACUGAAGAUAGCACGAAUCUCUGAUGUUUGCAAGUUCAGAAUAAAAUGGAAAUGAAAAUUCAUUAUGUGGCAGUCUCAGUACUGAGCACAAAGGCUUUUAACCACAAGCAAAUUACUGUGCUAGCCAGACCGUGUGAGAGAACUCCAGGCCAGCUUGCUAAAACUGAGCAGGAGAAUUUGGAGAGAGUCCAGAGGAGAGCCACAGAAACAACUGAAGCAUGACAAGAAUAAUUGCAGUUCUGUUAUAGAGAGGUCAUCUAUAUCAGGCUUUUAUGGAGUACCAUGUGGAAUGUUACCACGCAGAGCAUGGGGAACAGCUGUUGUGACUCAACAAGAGACAGGACAGAAGAAAUGAGAACAGGUGGAAGAUCAAUAAUUUAGGUUUGAUAUGGGGAAAGAUGGAACAGUCAAAGGGAUUCACACUGAUUUUUGGCUGAGCAGAAGGCAGAGUCUCCUCCAACGGGCAAUGUAAGUGCCCCCACUCAUCUACACCCCGAGAAGAGCCAUCAAACUGUAUUAAACUUGGAAAAAGCUAUUUAACUUCAAGUGUGCUGCGAGAAAACUUCAUAAUAGUUCCUAAGAUGUGCUAAAAAGUAAAGUCCAAAAAGAUCAUAAAGUCUGUAGAGAAGUUCUAAGAGUGCAGUCAGCUAUAAAAACCUAGCAAUUUAAUUUCUUAGAAAAAUGUAGCUGGAGUUCAAACUGUAGUAACAAAGGCAAGUAAAUUAAGUUGUGGGCAGGUGUAAUUAAGUUAAUAGGAAUGGCAGGGAUGAAUAUAAAUCAGAACAGGACUAACAGUUUGAAACAUUAGAUAUUCAAAUGCUCAGAGCUGAUGAGCCGAGCCACUACGCUAACAACUCUGCAAACCAAAGGUUUCACAAAUUGCACAAGAACCUGGCCUCGAUCCCAUUGUGUUGCUGGCAUAAGAUUAGAAGGGCCUGUUGGUUCAAUUGUUGCUUUGGACAGAGGAGGACAAACUUGCCACAGUGAAGAAAUCAUUUUUAAAAACCACCACUGUCCUUUAGUGCACUAAUUUCUCUAAUAACUAGGUGUAUAUUAGAAAUAAUGAUAUAUAAGUGCAGUAUACUCCAGUUUCAACAGAAUGGUGUCACUUCUGUAAAAUGUUGAUUUUCAGAUUGUCAUACUUUCUAAAUACAAAAAUUUGUCACAGCUUCCACAUUUACAAGAUAUUAAACAUUCCAUAAAAUAUUUGUAGAAAUAUGAAAAACCAAUUUUUGUAGUUGCCUUUUGAAAUGUAUACAAAAUAUCCCACAUGGGCAACAUGGUAAAACCUCGUCUCUACAAAAAAAAAAAAAAAAAUACAAAAAGUUAGCCAGGCCUGGUGGUGCACGCCUGUGGUCCCAGCUACUCGGGAAGCUGAAGUGAGAUCACCUGUGCCCAGGAGGUCGAAGCUGCAGUGAGCUGUGAUUGCACCACUGCACUCCAGCCUGGGUGACAGAGUGAGACUUUGUCUCAAAUAAACAAAAAGAGACAUAUACAAAAUAUAUUAGAAAGUUGGGUUAAUAUCCUACAAACAAAGUAUUACAUAGUUUGCACAGGAUUAUGUGUGUAAAAAGUUUUAAAUUCAGUAUAGCUUUUAUUUCUGCAGAACUAAAAGUAGUGCAUAAAAAUAAAAGUGGGAUGAGCAUAUCUUUUUAAUUUGCUAUGCAGUAAAAAGUAUCUCAGUCAACAUAUAGGAAACCAGUGCCAUUUCUGUAUCAUUUGACACCGAAGGGGUAUUGUUUUUUGUUUUGUUUUGUUUUUCUUUUGAAGAAAGACUUUUAUGUCUUUUAUUCUAUUCUUCCGAUUUGGGGUUUAAAUUACCCCCAAUAAGUUUGCAGAAUAUUCUGAUUACUACUGCUUAGGUGAUAUAUUUCAUAUGAGAACUAUCUUUACACAAUGGGAAAAAAUAUGGUAACCACUUCAUUCAUCAGAGAAGUUGUGUUUUGUUUACUUGUAUUUUGUUUGCUAAAUGAAAUUGGUUAUUUAGACUCAUGGCAUGCUUUUUCUCAAAUGGAGAUUUAAAAGUCAUUUCCAAUGUCCUUCUAACUUCUGGCCAAUUCCCAGUAGGCUAUAGAAUAAACAGUUUUCAUAUAAUAGUC